GUUUUAACAAACAAACAAGUUUUCUCUUUUUAACAAUUACCACAUUCUGCGCUUGGAUAUACAGCAGUGAACAAAAAAAAAAAAAAAAAUCUCCAGGCCUAACAUAAUUUCAGGAAGAAAUUUCAGUAGUUGUAUCUCAGGGGAAAUACAGGAAGUUAGCCUGGAGUAAAAGUCAGUCUGUCCCUGCCCCUUUGCUAUUUUGCCCGUGCCUCACAGUGCUCUCUGCCUGUGACGACAGCUCCGCAGAAGUUCGGAGGAUAUAAUGGAAUUCAUUGUGUACUGAAGAAUGGAUAGAGAACUCAAGAAGGAAAUUGGAAACUGGAAGCAAAUGUCAUGAUGAUGGGCAGCGCCCGAGUGGCGGAGCUGCUGCUGCUCCACGGCGCGGAGCCCAACUGCGCCGACCCCGCCACUCUCACCCGACCCGUGCACGACGCUGCCCGGGAGGGCUUCCUGGACACGCUGGUGGUGCUGCACCGGGCCGGGGCGCGGCUGGACGUGCGCGAUGCCUGGGGCCGUCUGCCCGUGGACCUGGCUGAGGAGCUGGGCCAUCGCGAUGUCGCACGGUACCUGCGCGCGGCUGCGGGGGGCACCAGAGGCAGUAACCAUGCCCGCAUAGAUGCCGCGGAAGGUCCCUCAGCUGGCUGGACCAACCUCAGGAUUUCCAAACCCAAUUGUGCGUGGCAUCAUCUGGAGAUCUCUCGAUCUCGGCUCUUCUGCACAACUCAACUAAUCUGACCCUCCUCAGCUAAUCUGACCCUCCGCUUUAUGCGGUAGAGUUUUCCAGAGCUGCCCCAGGGGGUUCUGGGGACAUCAGGACCAAGACUUCGCUGACCCUGGCAGUCUGUGCACCGGAGUUGGCUCCUUUCCCUCUUAAACUUGUGCAAGAGAUCGCUGAGCGAUGAAGGUAGAAUUAUGGUCCUCCUUGCCCUUGCCUUUCCUUUUUGUGAUCUCAAAGCAUCCUCCCUCCGCCCCCAUUCCAUGGCCCCAGUUCCCUACUCCCACAGCUGUCUGCUGAAACUGCCAACAUUACUCAAUUGUUUCUGGGGGGAGGAACAUUUUUUUUUGAAACAAAAUAGAUAUAUGAAACAGUACACGGGAAUUAACACGAAUAUUUAAGGUAAAACAUGACCUUGAAGAUUAUGAAAUCCAUCUUAUUUUGGCCCAGAACGGGGGCAUUGGGCUCCUUGGGCCAUAGGGGAGCUGGGGAGGACAGGGUGAAGAGUUAGCUCUAAGCCCUCUGCUUGGAGAUGCUGUAAAUACAGAACGCAAAAUCACCUUCGAAGUUAAAGACGCGAAGUUCUUCUUUACUCGGCCCCUCCUCCCCUCCCCCCCGCCA